UCUGUGAUGUGUCGCGGAGUUGCCGAUAGGGUUCGGUGUGGCGAGGAGGACCUGCUUCUCUCUUUGUGAGACAAGGGAGUGAGGGAGGAAGGAGGCCAAGGAGGAGGCCAGGACUGAGCAAGGACUAAAGUAAGACUGAAAGGGGAGGUGAGGGGUGGACUGGUUGGUGGCAGCAACCUGUACCGGAAGCGGCGGCGGCAGCCGAGGCGACGCACCGUGAGGCAGCUGCUUGACUAGGCCGCAGCCGCCAUGGCGAUGAACUUUGGGGACCAUGCCAGCGGGUUCCGCCAUGAUGAUGUGAUCAGGUUCAUCAACAAUGAAGUCCUCAGGAACGGCGGCAGCCCAGCCUUUUACACGGCCUUCCGCUCGCGGCCGUGGAACGAGGUAGAGGACCGGCUUCGGGCCAUUGUGGCCGACCCGCGGGUGCCCCGUGCCAUUAAGAGGGCCUGUACCUGGAGCGCUUUGGCGCUGAGUGUGCAAGUGGCUGCGAGGCAGCAGGAGGAGCUGCUGUACCAGGUUUGGUGGCUGCAAGGGCAUGUGGAGGAGUGCCAGGCGACCUCCUGGGCUCUAACUUCCCAGCUGCAGCAGCUGCGCCUGGAGCAUGAGGAGGUGGCAACACAGCUGCACCUCACGCAGGCCGCCCUGCAGCAGGUGCUGAAUGAGCGUGAUGGGUUAUGCGGGAGGCUGCUAGAAGUUGAGAGAUCCAUGCAGGUCUAUCCGAUGCCUCAGGAUUUUGUACCCGGUCCAGAAGCCGGCCAGUAUGGGCCUGUGGCCGGGACUUUAAAUGCAGAACAGAGUGAGGCGGUGGCCACAGAGGCACAGGGAAUGCCACAUUCGGAAGCCCAGGUAGCAGCCCCAACAGCUGUGUAUUACAUGCCUGAACCCCAGAGUGGCAGGGUCCAGGGCAUGCAACCUCUUCUGCUAAUGCAGGCACCUCAUCCAGUCCCAUUCCAUAUGCCUUCACCAAUGGGACUGCCAUACUCAACACCUCUACCACCCCCAGUAGUAAUGGAAUCAGCAGCAGCAAUUGCACCACAGAUGCCUCCUGCAGGGAUCUAUCCACCUGGUCUUUGGGCCACAGUGGGAUCCCAGGAGGAGACGGCCCCUCCGUGGGACCAGAAGUGCCAUGGCCAGGAUGGAUAUCCUGAGAAUUUCCAGGGAGUAUAUCACCCAGGAGAUAACAGAAGCUGCAACCAAAAGGAAGGUUCUGAGUGUCCCCAAGGAAUGACUUCCCAAGGGGACAGCAGCAGCCACAGCCUGAAGAAAGAUCCAGUGAUGCAAGAGGGCACAGCUCCCCCAGAGUUUAGCAGGAGCCACAGCCUGGAGAAAAAACCAGUGAUGCCCAAGGAGAUGGUCCCCCUAGGGGACAGCAACAGCCACAGCCUGAAGAAAGAUCCAGUUGUGCCCAAGGAGAUUGUCCCCAUAGGGGACAGCAACAGCCACAGCCUGACGAAAAAUCCAGUUGUGCACAAGGAGAUGGUCUCCCUGGGGGACAGCAACAGCCACAGCAUGAAGAAAGAUCCAGUGAUGCCCCAGAAGAUGGUCCCCCUGGGGGACAGCAACAGCCACAGUCUGAAGAAAGAUCCAAUGAUGUGCCAGGAGAUGGUCCCCCUGGGGGACAGCAACAGCCAUAGCCUGAAGAAAGAUCCAGUGGUGGCCCAGGGCACAGCUCCCCUGAUGUAUAGCAGGAGGCACAGCCAGAAGAAAGUGCCAAUGAUGCCCAAGGAGAUGGUCCCCCUGGGGGAAAGCCACAGCCACAGCCUGAAGAAAGAUCUAGUUGUGCCCAAGGAGCUGGUCCCCCUGGGGGACAGCAAGAGUCACAGGAUGAAGAAAGAUCCAGUGAUGCCCCAGAAGAUGGUCCCCCUGGGGGACAGCAGAAGCCACAGCCUGAAGAAAGAUCCAGUGAUGCCCCAGAACAUGAUCCCCCUGGAGGACAGCAACAGCCACAGCCUGAAGAAAGAUCCAGUGAUGCCCCAGAACAUGAUCCCCCUGGAGGACAGCAACAGCCACAGUCUGAAGAAAGAUCCAAUGAUGCACCAGGAGAUGGUCCCCCUGGGGGACAGCAACAGCCAUAGCCUGAAGAAAGAUCCAGUGGUGCCCCAGGACACAGCUCCCCUGAUGUUUAGCAGGAGACACAGCCUGAAGAAAGUGCCAGUGAUGCCCAAGGAGAUGGUCCCCCUGGGGGACAGCCACAGCCUGAAGAAAGAUCCAGUGAUGCCCCAGAACAUGGUCCCCCUGGAGGACAGCAACAGCCAUAGCCUGAAGAAAGAUCCAGUGGUGCCCCAGGGCACAGCUCCCCUGAUGUUUAGCAGGAGACACAGCCUGAAGAAAGUGCCAGUGAUGCCCAAGGAGAUGGUCCCCCUGGGGGACAGCAACAGCCAUAGCCUGAAGAAAGAUCCAGUGGUGCCCCAGGGCACAGCUCCCCUGAUGUUUAGCAGGAGACACAGCCUGAAGAAAGUGCCAGUGAUGCCCAAGGAGAUGGUCCCCCUGGGGGACAGCCACAGCCUGAAGAAAGAUCCAGUGAUGCCCCAGAACAUGGUCCCCCUGGAGGACAGCAACAGCCAUAGCCUGAAGAAAGAUCCAGUGGUGCCCCAGGGCACAGCUCCCCUGACGUUUAGCAGGAGACACAGCCUGAAGAAAGUGCCAGUGGUGCCCCAGGGGACAGCCUCCCUGGGGUUCAGCAGAAUCCACAGCCUGAAGAAAGAGUUAGUGAUGCCCGAGGAGAUGGUCCCCCUGGGGGACAGCAACAGCCACAGCAUGAAGAAAGAUCUAGUGAUGCCCAAGGAGAUGGUCCCCCUAGGGGACAGCAACAGUCACAGCCUGAAGAAAGAUCCAGUGGUGCACCAGGAGGUGGUCUCCUUGGGGGACAGCAACAGCCACAGCCUGAAGAAACAUCCAGUGAUUCCCCAGGGCACAGCCUCACUGAGGUUUAGCAAGAGCCACAGCCAGAAGGAAGAUCAGGAGAGGCCCCAGGUAACCCCUCUGGAGGAUAGCAAGAGCCAUGGUGUGAAAAAUAGCCCAUGGAAACACCAGCCUCAGGGGCAGAAGGUCAAGGAACAAAAAAGGAAAAAGGCCUCAGAAUCCCAGCAACAGAAGCCUGCCUCAUGCUCCAGCCCAGUGAAUUGGGCCUGCCCAUGGUGUAAUGCCAUGAAUUUUCCACGGAACAAGGUGUGCUCUAAAUGCAAGAGAGUCCGUAUGCCAGUUGAGAAUGGCAGCGUUGACCCAGCGUAAACUCAUUGAUUUCAGGAAGUUUUACAGGUGAAGUCCUGUUUUUGUGUCUUAGCUCCACCAAACUUGCUUGUUUCUGAAGAAGCUGAACCUGUGACAUUAGAAGAUCUGCCAAAGCCACAAGAAGUAACACCUCAAUUCUGAUGGACCCACACCUCACUGAGACCCCAACUGGCUGCAGUCAAGAAGAGUGAAAGGAAGUCAGGGAAGAAGAGAUCAUUUGACACUCAUUAGGGGGAAAAGGGAGAACAAAAUUGUUUUUGUAGAGUUGAAUUUUUUCAUUGGUAUGGGAAUUAACUUAGAAAAGUUUGGGGAGUUGUAGUGUUAAAUUCUAUAGAUGGUAGCAACUUUGAUGAAUUUCACUUAAUUCAUUAAAUGAGAAGUUUAGGGAAAGAGUUUAGGGGGUUGUAGUGUUAAAUUCUAUAGCUGAUAGCAACUUUAAUUAAUUUCAUUUAAUUCAUUAAAGAAAUAGUUAUUGCCUAGUAUGUUUUGGGAGCUAGACUUGUAUGUUAUUAUCUAGUACACACAGCAUAAUCUUUUAUUGUGAAUUCGGUUAGAAGAUAGGAAAGAGCAUAAUUUGGCAUACACAUUAGAUCAGGGAUGUAUUCUUUGCCUUGCAUAUAGCGUGACCUUGGAUAAAACCAAUUGAAGUAACAUCCAGAUCCAUUUCUGUGGUUCUGGGGCCAAUGCGAAAGAGACUUUCAUGAAAGGUUUUUUGUUUUGUUUUUGUUUUUUUUAAUUUUUUGGAGAAAUGAGGUCUCAUUUUGUCGCCCAGGCUGGAGUGCAGUGGCAUGAUCAUCAUAGCUCACUGCAGCCUCAAACUCCUGGGCUCAAGUGAUCCUCUGCCUCAGCCUCCCGAGUGGCUGUGAGCCACCAUGCCCAGCCCUUAUGAAAGGUCUUGAGUAACCAAACUGCUUGUCUCAUUGGUCUCAGGUGAGAUAAAUGAGCAGUGACAAAGUUUGGGAAAGUGUCCUCACAAAAAUGCAGGCAGAGCUUUUCUGAAUUCCUCUGCUGAUUUCCUCCUUUGAGAAGGAUAGCUAUUUUCCUGGUUGCCCACCAGCCUGCCUGAAAGACCUGGGGUGUCUUGAAGAAAAACAGUGCUUUGGGGAGUGUUCACUACACACGCUAGCUUUCAGCCUCAGGCUGCCCCCAUCCCAAGUCCCUUUUCAGUCAGCAGUGGAUGAAGAACAAAAUGGAUUCCAAGGACAAACAUUGGGGGCACCAGGUUAUGGAUGGUGUUUCUCUUGGGAGGAUAAAUUGGGUUAAAAAUAGAGCUAGACUGGGGCAAGCACUUUUGGGAAUACCCCAGGACCCCCACCUCUCCCUCUUUGGUGUGUUCUCUGCAGGCUUACCCAAGGCAACUGCUGCAAGGCAAGGAAGGAGCCAGGGUGGAGCCCAGGGGUGGUUGGUUAGAUCUGCCUUCAAUCCAAGCUAAAGAUGUCCUUGAGUUUCCCAAUGAGAUCCCACCCAGCUCACCAAAAUCAAUGUUUGUCAGGGAUUUUCUGGGCCUAACUAGUAAUAAAGAAUGUGCAUUUGA